AUGGCUCUCAAGGAGGGACUCAGGGCCUGGAAGAGAAUCUUCUGGCGGCAGAUCCUACUUACACUUGGCCUCUUAGGCCUGUUUCUGUAUGGCCUCCCUAAAUUCAGGCAUCUGGAAGCCCUCAUCCCCAUGGGCGUCUGCCCUUCGGCCACAAUGUCCCAGCUGAGAGACAACUUCACAGGUGCCCUGCGUCCCUGGGCCCGGCCUGAAGUUCUGACCUGUACCCCCUGGGGGGCUCCCAUUAUUUGGGAUGGCUCUUUCGACCCAGAUGUGGCCAAGCAAGAGGCUAGACAGCAGAACCUCACCAUUGGGCUGACUAUCUUUGCUGUAGGCAGAUACCUGGAGAAGUACCUGGAGCGCUUCCUGGAGACGGCGGAGCAGCACUUCAUGGCGGGCCAGAGCGUGAUGUACUACGUGUUCACCGAGCUUCCGGGAGCGGUGCCCCGCGUGGCGCUGGGCCCGGGACGCCGGCUGCCCGUGGAGCGCGUGGCGCGCGAGCGGCGCUGGCAAGACGUGUCGAUGGCGCGCAUGCGCACGUUGCACGCGGCGCUGGGCGGGCUGCCGGGCCGCGAGGCGCACUUCAUGUUCUGCAUGGACGUGGACCAGCACUUCAGCGGCACUUUUGGGCCCGAGGCGCUGGCCGAGUCGGUGGCGCAGCUGCACUCCUGGCACUACCACUGGCCGUCGUGGCUGCUGCCCUUCGAACGCGACGCGCAUUCGGCCGCCGCGAUGGCGUGGGGCCAGGGCGACUUCUAUAACCACGCGGCGGUGUUCGGGGGCAGCGUGGCGGCGCUGCGCGGGCUGACGGCGCACUGUGCGGGGGGCCUGGACUGGGACCGCGCGCGCGGCCUGGAGGCGCGCUGGCACGACGAGAGCCACCUCAACAAGUUCUUCUGGCUGCACAAGCCCGCCAAGGUGCUGUCGCCCGAGUUCUGCUGGAGCCCGGACAUCGGCCCGCGGGCCGAGAUCCGCCGCCCGCGACUGCUGUGGGCGCCCAAGGGGUACCGGCUGCUGCGGAACUAG